AGGUUGCAAAAGAAGAAUGGUCUCAGACCCUUUGGAUCAACCUGAAUGUGCAGAUUCUCCAGGAAGGAAUUGAAGGUUUUCUCAGGGCUCUCAGAAAGCUACCUCGGCCAGUCCGUGGCUUAUCAGUGACCUACUACUUGGAAGCAAAAAUGAAGGCAUUCAAAGACUCGAUUCCUUUACUUCUUGACUUGAAAAACGAGGCACUAAGAGACAGGCAUUGGAAAGAACUUAUGGAAAAAACGUCUGUCUUUUUUGAAAUGACCGAAACGUUCACCUUGGAAAAUAUGUUUGCUAUGGAACUGCACAAACACACAGAUGUUCUCAAUGAGAUUGUCACAGCAGCAAUCAAGGAGGUUGCCAUUGAGAAGGCUGUGAAGGAAAUCCUAGACACGUGGGAAAAUAUGAAAUUCACUGUAGUCAAGUAUUGCAAAGGCACACAGGAGCGAGGCUACAUCCUGGGUUCUGUUGACGAAAUUAUUCAGUCUCUUGAUGACAACACUUUCAACCUGCAGAGCAUCUCAGGAAGCAGAUUUGUGGGGCCUUUUCUGCAAACUGUUCACAAAUGGGAAAAAACGCUUUCUCUAAUAGGGGAAGUCAUUGAGAUUUGGAUGUUGGUUCAGAGAAAAUGGAUGUAUCUUGAAAGUAUUUUUAUUGGUGGAGAUAUAAGAUCACAACUUCCGGAAGAGGCAAAAAAGUUUGACAACAUCGAUAAAGUAUUUAAAAGGAUCAUGGGUGAGACCUUAAAAGACCCCGUGAUCAAGAGGUGCUGUGAAGCCCCAAACCGCCUCAGUGACCUACAGAACGUCAGCGAGGGCCUGGAGAAAUGCCAGAAAAGCCUCAACGACUACUUAGAUUCGAAGAGAAAUGCUUUCCCAAGGUUCUUCUUCAUUUCUGACGAUGAGUUGCUUAGCAUUCUGGGGAGCAGCGACCCACUCUGCGUCCAGGAGCACAUGAUCAAGAUGUACGACAACAUAGCAUCACUGAGGUUUAAUGACGGCGAUAGUGGAGAAAAACUGGUGUCCGCGAUGAUUUCAGCAGAAGGAGAAGUCAUGGAGUUUCGGAAGAUCUUGCGGGCUGAAGGGCGCGUGGAGGACUGGAUGACGGCAGUUUUGAAUGAGAUGAGAAGAACUAAUAGACUAAUUACCAAAGAGGCUAUUUUUAGAUACUGUGAAGACAGAAGCAGAGUCGACUGGAUGCUCCUGUACCAGGGCAUGGUGGUGCUGGCCGCUAGCCAGGUGUGGUGGACCUGGGAGGUGGAAGACGUCUUCCACAAAGCGCAAAAAGGGGAGAAGCAGGCCAUGAAGAACUAUGGCAGGAAAAUGCACCGGCAGAUCGAUGAGUUGGUAACGCGCAUCACCAUGCCGCUAAGCAAAAACGACAGGAAAAAAUACAACACUGUUCUCAUCAUUGAUGUGCAUGCCAGAGACAUAGUUGAUUCUUUCAUAAGAGGCAGUAUCCUGGAGGCCCGAGAGUUUGACUGGGAAAGUCAGUUGCGGUUUUAUUGGGACCGGGAGCCGGAUGAGCUGAACAUCCGCCAGUGCACGGGAACCUUUGGCUACGGCUACGAGUACAUGGGCCUGAACGGCAGGCUGGUCAUCACGCCCCUCACCGAUCGGAUUUACCUGACGCUCACCCAGGCGCUGUCCAUGUAUCUAGGUGGGGCCCCCGCCGGCCCAGCAGGAACCGGCAAAACCGAGACCACCAAGGACCUGGCGAAAGCCUUGGGCUUGCUCUGUGUUGUCACCAACUGUGGCGAAGGCAUGGAUUACAGGGCCGUGGGGAAGAUUUUCUCUGGCCUGGCACAGUGCGGGGCUUGGGGCUGCUUUGAUGAGUUUAAUCGAAUCGAUGCUUCUGUGCUCUCCGUGAUCUCCUCCCAGAUCCAGACGAUCCGAAAUGCUCUGAUCCAUCAGUUAACCACGUUCCAGUUUGAAGGGCAGGAGAUUUCCCUGGACUCCCGCAUGGGCAUCUUCAUCACCAUGAACCCCGGCUACGCAGGCCGCACGGAGCUGCCCGAGUCGGUGAAGGCGCUGUUCAGGCCUGUGGUCGUGAUCGUGCCCGACCUGCAGCAGAUCUGUGAGAUCAUGCUCUUCUCUGAGGGCUUCCUGGAGGCCAAGACUCUGGCGAAAAAGAUGACGGUUCUGUAUAAGCUGGCCCGGGAGCAGCUGUCCAAGCAGUAUCACUAUGAUUUUGGACUCAGAGCCCUGAAAUCGGUGCUGGUCAUGGCUGGUGAGCUGAAGAGAGGCUCCUCUGACCUUAGGGAGGACGUGGUGCUGAUGAGGGCCUUGCGAGACAUGAACUUGCCCAAAUUUGUGUUUGAAGAUGUUCCUCUUUUCCUUGGUUUGAUUUCGGAUCUGUUUCCUGGGCUGGACUGCCCUCGCGUCCGCUACCCUGACUUCAACGAUGCGGUAGAGCAGGUCCUGGAGGAGAACGGCUACGCGGUCCUACCCAUCCAGGUGGAUAAAGUGGUUCAAAUGUUCGAGACCAUGUUAACCCGCCACACGACGAUGGUGGUGGGGCCCACCAGAGGGGGCAAGUCCGUCGUCAUUAACACUCUGUGUCAGGCCCAGACCAAGCUUGGGCUGACGACAAAGUUGUACAUCCUGAACCCCAAAGCCGUGAGUGUCAUAGAACUCUACGGCAUCCUGGACCCAACCACCCGAGACUGGACAGAUGGGGUGUUGUCAAACAUCUUCAGGGAAAUCAACAAGCCAACAGACAAGAAGGAGCGAAAGUAUAUUUUAUUUGAUGGUGAUGUGGAUGCUCUAUGGGUGGAAAACAUGAAUUCUGUGAUGGAUGACAACAGGUUGUUGACAUUGGCCAACGGGGAACGCAUCCGGCUCCAAGCACACUGUGCCCUGCUCUUUGAGGUUGGAGAUUUACAGUAUGCCUCCCCUGCAACUGUCUCUCGAUGUGGAAUGGUUUAUGUGGAUCCUAAAAACUUGAAAUAUCGACCAUACUGGAAAAAAUGGGUUAAUCAAAUACCAAACAAGGUGGAGCAAUACAAUUUGAAUAGUCUCUUUGAGAAGUAUGUGCCCUAUCUCAUGGAUGUGAUAGUGGAAGGAAUUGUGGAUGGAAGACAAGCAGAAAAGCUGAAGACAAUAGUUCCUCAGACAGACCUCAAUAUGGUAACCCAGUUAGCCAAGAUGUUGGAUGCGUUGCUAGAAGGAGAAAUAGAAGACCUUGACCUGCUGGAGUGCUACUUCCUGGAGGCUUUGUACUGCUCUCUGGGAGCCUCCCUGCUUGAGGAUGGAAGGAUGAAAUUUGACGAAUAUAUCAAACGCCUUGCUUCUUUGUCUACUGUUGACACAGAAGGAGUUUGGGCCAACCCUGGGGAACUGCCAGGUCAACUUCCAACCUUGUAUGACUUUCAUUUUGAUAACAAACGGAAUCAAUGGGUCCCAUGGAGUAAAUUAGUUCCAGAGUAUAUUCAUGCCCCCGAGAGGAAAUUCAUCAACAUCCUGGUUCACACAGUGGAUACCACUCGGACUACCUGGAUAUUGGAACAAAUGGUUAAAAUUAAGCAACCUGUUAUUUUUGUUGGUGAAUCUGGCACUUCUAAGACAGCCACUACCCAGAAUUUCCUCAAAAAUCUGAGUGAAGAAACUAACAUUGUGUUAAUGGUCAACUUCUCCUCCCGCACCACGUCCAUGGAUAUCCAAAGAAAUUUAGAAGCAAAUGUGGAAAAGCGAACCAAAGAUACUUACGGCCCACCCAUGGGAAAACGCCUGCUGGUGUUCAUGGAUGACAUGAAUAUGCCAAGGGUGGAUGAAUAUGGCACGCAGCAGCCCAUUGCCUUGCUGAAGCUGCUGUUGGAAAAAGGCUACUUAUAUGACCGUGGGAAGGAGCUGAACUGUAAAAGCAUUCGAGACCUUGGCUUUAUUGCUGCAAUGGGAAAGGCUGGAGGAGGCCGCAAUGAAGUUGACCCAAGAUUUAUUUCGCUAUUCAGUGUCUUCAAUGUGCCAUUUCCUUCAGAGGAGUCUCUGCAUUUAAUUUAUUCCUCCAUCCUGAAAGGCCACACCUCGACGUUUCAUGAGAGCAUUGUGGCUGUGAGUGGCAAGCUGACAUUCUGCACGCUAGCACUUUACAAAAAUAUUGUGCAAGACCUACCUCCCACUCCGUCAAAGUUCCAUUACAUCUUCAACCUUCGAGAUCUCUCACGGGUUUUUAAUGGUCUUGUCCUCACUAACCCGGAGCGAUUCCAGACGGUGGCCCAGAUGGUGAGAGUCUGGAGGAAUGAGUGUCUGAGAGUCUUCCACGACCGGCUGAUCAGUGAAACAGACAAGCAGCUGGUACAACAGCACAUAGGCAGCUUGGUUGUGGAACAUUUUAAAGAUGACGUGGAGGUGGUGAUGAGGGAUCCCAUAUUGUUUGGAGACUUCCAGAUGGCUCUGCACGAAGGAGAACCACGCAUUUAUGAAGACAUCCAGGACUACGAGGCGGCCAAGGCUCUGUUCCAGGAAAUUCUUGAAGAGUAUAAUGAAAGCAACACCAAAAUGAACUUGGUUCUCUUCGACGAUGCUCUGGAGCAUUUAACCCGGGUGCACCGUAUCAUCCGCAUGGACCGCGGCCACGCCCUGCUGGUCGGGGUAGGGGGCUCAGGGAAGCAGUCUCUUUCGAGGCUGGCUGCCUUCACAGCCAGCUGUGAGGUGUUUGAGAUCCUGCUGAGCCGAGGCUACUCGGAGAACAGUUUCCGGGAAGACCUGAAGAGCCUCUAUUUGAAACUUGGGAUUGAGAACAAAGCGAUGAUCUUUCUGUUCACGGAUGCCCAUGUGGCUGAGGAGGGCUUCCUGGAGCUCAUCAACAACAUGCUGACCUCAGGAAUUGUACCUGCGCUUUUUUCUGAAGAGGAGAAAGAGUCUAUCCUGAGUCAGAUUGGACAGGAAGCUCUGAAGCAAGGCAUGGGGCCGGCCAAGGAGUCUGUGUGGCAGUACUUCGUGAACAAAAGUGCAAAUAACCUGCACAUUGUCCUGGGCAUGUCGCCAGUGGGGGACACCCUGAGGACCUGGUGCAGAAACUUCCCAGGUAUGGUAAAUAACACUGGUAUUGACUGGUUCAUGCCCUGGCCUCCCCAAGCCCUCCAUGCGGUCGCAAAGUCCUUUCUAGGGUAUAAUCCAAUGAUCCCGGCAGAAAAUAUAGAAAAUGUGGUGAAGCAUGUUGUCUUGGUUCACCAAUCCGUGGACCACUACAGCCAACAGUUUCUACAGAAAUUGAGGCGCAGCAACUAUGUCACUCCCAAGAACUACCUUGAUUUUAUUAACACCUAUUCAAAAUUGCUGGAUGAGAAAACUCAGUGUAAUAUAGCUCAGUGCAAGCGUCUGGAUGGGGGACUGGACAAGCUGAAGGAGGCCACCAUCCAGCUGGACGAGCUGAACCAGAAGCUGGCCGAGCAGAAGAUCGUGCUGGCGGAGAAGUCCGCCGCCUGCGAGGCCUUGCUGGAGGAGAUCGCCGUCAACACCGCUGUAGCCGAGGAGAAGAAGAAACUGGCAGAGGAAAAGGCCAUGGAGAUAGAGGAGCAGAACAAAGUCAUUGCCAUGGAGAAGGCCGAGGCCGAGACGACCCUGGCAGAGGUCAUGCCCAUCCUGGAGGCCGCCAAGCUGGAACUGCAGAAGCUGGACAAGUCGGACGUGACUGAGAUUAGGUCGUUUGCUAAGCCCCCGAAGCAGGUGCAGACGGUCUGCGAAUGCAUCCUCAUCAUGAAAGGGUACAAAGAGCUGAACUGGAAAACAGCCAAGGGCGUGAUGUCCGACCCGAAUUUCCUGCGGUCUCUGAUGGAGAUUGAUUUUGAUUCGAUUACCCAGAGCCAAGUGAAAAACAUCAAAGGCCUCUUGAAGACUCUUAAUACCACAACUGAAGAAAUGGAAGCUGUCAGCAAAGCCGGGCUGGGGAUGCUGAAAUUUGUUGAAGCUGUAAUGGGCUACUGUGAUGUUUUCAGAGAAAUCAAGCCCAAAAGAGAGAAGGUGGCCAGGCUGGAGCGGAAUUUUUACCUCACUAAACGGGAACUGGAAAGGAUCCAGAAUGAGUUGGCAGCAAUUCAGAAAGAGCUGGAAACAUUGGGUGCCAAAUAUGAGGCCGCCAUACUGGAAAAGCAGAAGCUGCAGGAAGAAGCCGAGAUCAUGGAGAGGCGGCUGAUUGCCGCAGACAAACUCAUCUCGGGUCUGGGGUCAGAAAACAUCAGGUGGCUGAACGACCUGGAUGAGCUGAUGCACCGGCGCGUGAAGCUGCUGGGGGACUGCCUGCUCUGCGCGGCUUUCCUCAGCUACGAGGGAGCCUUCACCUGGGAGUUCCGUGACGAGAUGGUCAAUCGGAUUUGGCAAAAUGACAUCCUGGAGCGGGAGAUCCCCCUGAGCCAGCCUUUCCGGCUGGAAAGCCUGCUCACGGAUGAUGUUGAGAUCAGCAGAUGGGGAUCCCAGGGCCUUCCCCCCGAUGAGCUCUCCGUUCAGAAUGGCAUCCUCACCACCCGGGCCAGCCGCUUCCCUCUGUGUAUCGACCCCCAGCAGCAGGCCCUCAACUGGAUCAAGAGAAAAGAGGAGAAGAACAAUCUGCGGGUCGCUUCCUUUAAUGACCCUGACUUCCUCAAGCAGCUAGAGAUGUCCAUAAAGUACGGGACCCCUUUCCUGUUCCGCGAUGUUGAUGAAUACAUCGAUCCUGUGAUUGACAACGUCUUAGAAAAAAAUAUAAAAGUCUCCCAAGGACGGCAGUUUAUUAUCCUGGGAGACAAGGAAGUGGACUAUGAUUCAAAUUUCAGACUGUACCUGAACACCAAGCUGGCCAAUCCCAGAUAUUCCCCAUCCGUGUUUGGGAAAGCUAUGGUGAUCAAUUACACUGUCACGCUGAAGGGCCUGGAGGACCAGCUGCUGAGCGUGCUGGUGGCUUACGAGAGGCGGGAGCUGGAGGAGCAGCGGGAGCACCUCAUCCAGGAGACCAGCGAGAACAAGAACCUGCUCAAGGACCUGGAAGAUUCCCUCCUUCGGGAGCUGGCCACGUCCACGGGGAACAUGCUGGACAAUGUGGACCUGGUGCACACCCUGGAGGAGACCAAAUCCAAGGCAACAGAGGUCUCAGAGAAACUCAAGCUGGCGGAGAAGACAGCCUUGGACAUCGACAGGCUGCGGGAUGGCUACCGGCCAGCAGCCAGGAGGGGGGCCAUCCUGUUCUUCGUCCUGUCUGAGAUGGCCCUGGUGAACUCCAUGUACCAGUACUCCCUGAUUGCCUUCUUAGAGGUCUUCAGGCUGUCACUGAAGAAGUCGCUGCCUGAUUCCAUCCUCAUGAAACGCCUGAGGAACAUCAUGGACACGCUGACCUUCAGCAUCUAUAACCACGGCUGCACAGGGCUGUUUGAGAGGCACAAGCUACUCUUUUCUUUUAAUAUGACCAUCAAGAUAGAACAAGCAGAAGGGAGAGUCCCUCAAGAAGAACUAGAUUUCUUUUUAAAAGGAAACAUUUCCCUGGAGAAAAGCAAAAGAAAAAAGCCCUGCGCUUGGUUGUCUGACCAAGGAUGGGAAGAUAUCAUUCUUUUAUCAGAAAUGUUUUCAGACAACUUUGGGCAACUUCCUGAUGAUGUUGAGAAUAAUCAGACUGUCUGGCAGGAGUGGUAUGACCUGGAUUCACUGGAGCAGUUUCCCGUCCCCUUGGGUUACGAUAACAACAUCACCCCUUUCCAGAAGUUGCUUAUUUUGCGCUGUUUCCGUGUGGAUCGGGUCUAUCGGGCCGUGACUGACUAUGUGACUGUAACAAUGGGAGAGAAGUAUGUGCAGCCCCCAAUGAUCAGCUUUGAAGCUAUUUUUGAGCAGAGCACUCCACAUUCGCCCAUUGUGUUUAUCCUGAGUCCUGGCUCCGACCCUGCCACUGAUCUUAUGAAAUUAGCAGAGCGAAGUGGUUUUGGAGGAAAUCGCCUCAAAUUCCUUGCAAUGGGUCAAGGUCAAGAAAAGGUGGCCCUGCAGCUGCUGGAGACGGCGGUGGCUCGGGGGCAGUGGCUGAUGCUGCAGAACUGCCACCUCCUGGUCAAGUGGCUGAAAGAUCUGGAGAAGUCCCUGGAGAGGAUCACCAAGCCCCACCCAGACUUCCGCCUGUGGCUCACCACGGACCCCACCAAGGGCUUCCCCAUUGGGAUUCUGCAGAAGUCCCUAAAGGUUGUCACCGAGCCACCCAAUGGGCUGAAACUCAACAUGAGGGCAACUUACUUCAAGAUCUCUCACGAAAUGCUGGACCAGUGCCCGCACCCUGCCUUCAAGCCGCUGGUCUACGUGCUGGCGUUCUUUCAUGCUGUGGUGCAGGAGAGAAGGAAGUUUGGGAAGAUUGGCUGGAACGUGUACUAUGACUUCAAUGAGUCUGACUUCCAGGUCUGCAUGGAAAUUCUGAACACGUACUUAACGAAAGCCUUCCAGCAACGGGACCCAAGGAUCCCGUGGGGCAGCCUCAAGUACCUAAUUGGAGAGGUCAUGUAUGGAGGACGGGCCAUCGACAGCUUUGAUCGCCGCAUCCUGACCAUCUACAUGGAUGAGUACCUGGGGGACUUCAUUUUUGAUACUUUCCAGCCAUUCCACUUCUUCCGGAACAAGGAAGUGGACUACAAAAUCCCUGUUGGUGAUGAAAAGGAGAAAUUUGUUGAAGCCAUCGAGGCCCUCCCGCUUGCCAACACGCCAGAAGUGUUUGGUCUCCACCCCAACGCUGAGAUUGGCUAUUACACGCAGGCGGCUCGAGACAUGUGGGCUCACCUGCUGGAGCUGCAGCCUCAGACAGGGGAAUCCAGCAGUGGUAUCAGCCGCGAUGAUUAUAUUGGCCAAGUGGCCAAAGAAAUAGAAAACAAGAUGCCCAAAGUCUUUGACUUGGACCAGGUGAGGAAGCGCCUCGGAACAGGACUCUCCCCCACUUCGGUGGUGCUCCUGCAGGAACUGGAACGCUUCAACAAGCUUGUGGUCCGGAUGACGAAGUCUCUGGCUGAACUUCAAAGGGCCUUGGCUGGAGAAGUUGGAAUGAGCAAUGAGUUAGAUGAUGUGGCCAGGUCUCUUUUUAUCGGGCAUAUCCCUAAUAUCUGGAGAAGGCUUGCUCCUGACACCUUAAAGUCCCUUGGAAACUGGAUGGUCUACUUCCUGCGGCGGUUCAGCCAGUACAUGUUGUGGGUGACCGAGAGCGAGCCCAGCGUGAUGUGGCUCUCGGGGCUGCACAUCCCUGAGUCCUACCUCACGGCGCUGGUGCAGGCCACCUGCCGGAAGAACGGCUGGCCACUGGACCGCUCCACCUUGUUCACACAAGUGACCAAGUUCCAGGAUGCAGAUGAAGUGAAUGAGCGGGCGGGACAAGGAUGCUUUGUCUCAGGACUGUACCUGGAAGGUGCUGACUGGGAUAUAGAAAAAGGAUGUCUUAUCAAGAGCAAACCCAAGGUGCUGGUUGUGGACCUGCCGAUCCUGAAGAUCAUCCCCAUUGAAGCCCAUCGCCUCAAGCUGCAGAAUACUUUCCGGACCCCCGUCUACACCACCUCCAUGAGAAGGAACGCCAUGGGAGUCGGCUUGGUUUUUGAAGCUGAUCUCUUUACCACGAGGCACAUUUCUCACUGGGUGCUGCAAGGAGUAUGCCUCACCCUGAAUUCUGAUUAACCUUUGGGUGAAGAAAACUGCUUAAUGAAUUCGGAGCCUGGGGUUGUCAGAGUGAUCGGGUCUGCUGUCAUUUCUUGGGGCCUCUCAAGAGGCAGGAGGGGGACUGACACUGAUUUUUCAUUUGAAAUCAGCCACUUAAAUCUCUUUCCAUACAAAUUAACCUGAAUGGUUUUGUUUUUAAUACUACUUUUUAAAAGGAAUUUAUAUAAUCAAAAAGUAAAUAUUGGAGAGUAUUUUAA